GCAGGAAGCAGCGGAACGAUUCGAUUCUUCUCAGCACCAAGUUGCGCUCCCAAUCUCUCAGAGCUGGGCUCGCGGGAGGCCGCUCGUGCAAAACCUAGGCUGAGCUCCCCUGCGCGGAGCUGUGAGCCCUGGAACACCGUGGUCUGCUUCUCAGGACGCGCAAACAGUGAAGCCAGUCCCGCCCGGGUGAGCCGCGGGGGCCUCUGGGAAGCGUCGCCCCUGGUGUAACGGACCGAGACUUGUGGCGCUCUCAGCCACCGACAGCGCCGGCCUCAGUGCCGCCUCUGUCCCAGCCCGCGCCGGCUCUGCCACUUUGGCAGCGUUAAGUGUGGAAUCGGGGCCUGUGUCCGCGGGCUUGGUGGUGAGUCCUCGGGAAACCGCUAGCUCUGAGCGCCGGACUCUUUGUGCUGGGUGGGAGUGGGGGCCCGCGGUCCUGGUGCCCCAAUCUUUGGAGGAGGACGCCGGGCGGGGCGAUGCCUGUGCUUGUGGUUCCCUGAGGCAGUGGGAGUGGCGUGUGAAGGACUGUGAGAGUCUGGCGUGAAGUGACUGUCAUUUGCCAGACAUUCGUCUGGCUGAGUGUGGCCCCGGGAUCGUGUCCGUAAGCGGAUUUCGUGGAGGCGCUUUCCCUUUUAUCUUUCAGUAUGAACCUGCGUGCAAACGUGCAUGACAGUGGGAUCUUGAAUGAAUGAAAAACUGUGGAUACAAGAGUUCUUCAUAUAUUAAGGAUUCAUUCAUUCAUAGACUCAUUUAUUGAAGGCUGUCUGUGUAACAGGCACAAUCCUAGGUGCUUGGGAUAUAGCAGUGAACAAGAGACAAACCCCCUACUAUCAUGGUACUUACAUUUUUGUGGGCUGGAUAAUAAACAAGGGAUGUAAACAGCUGGAAAGAACUUUGCUUCAAUCAUUACAACAAGGAAACUACAAACUUCUACCGUACAACAAGGAAAUGGACAAACUACAAAAUAAUUUUUCUAGGACCCUUCAGAGAACUGAGGUCACAGGGCAACCAAGUAAUCUUAAAUCUGGGGAAAGAAAGAUGCCAGCUGAGAGAAACAGGACUCAAGCUUUACUUACCUGGGAUGGACUCUGCCAGACACCAUAUAAGCCACUCUACUUCUGCAGGCCCCAUCCCUUCCCAGAAAGAAGAGGAAAUGACUGAGUCCCAGGGAACAGUAACAUUCAAAGAUGUGGCUAUCGACUUCACUCAGGAGGAGUGGAAGAGAUUGGAUCCUGCUCAGAGAAAACUGUACCGGAAUGUGAUGCUAGAAAACUAUAACAACUUAAUCACAGUAGGCUAUCCGUUCACCAAACCUGAUGUGAUUUUCAAAUUGGAGCAAGAAGAAGAACCAUGGGUGAUGGAGGAAGAAGUAUUAAGGAGACACUGGCAAGGAGAAAUAUGGGGAGUUGAUGAGCAUCAGAAAAACCAGGACAGACUUUUGAGACAAGUUGAAGUUAAAUUCCAGAAAACACUGACUGAAGAAAAAGGCAAUGAAUGUCAAAAGAAAUUUGCAAAUGUAUUUCCUCUGAACUCUGAUUUUUUCCCUUCCAGACACAAUCUCUAUGAGUAUGACUUAUUUGGAAAGUGUUUAGAACAUAAUUUUGACUGUCAUAAUAAUGUGAAAUGCCUUAUGAGAAAGGAGCAUUGUGAAUAUAAUGAACCUGUGAAAUCAUAUGGUAAUAGCUCAUCCCAUUUUGUCAUUACCCCCUUUAAGUGUAAUCAUUGUGGAAAAGGCUUCAAUCAGACUUUGGACCUCAUCAGACAUCUGAGAAUUCAUACUGGAGAGAAGCCCUAUGAAUGUAGUAACUGUAGAAAAGCCUUCAGUCACAAGGAAAAACUUAUUAAACAUUAUAAAAUUCACAGUAGGGAGCAGUCUUACAAAUGUAAUGAAUGUGGUAAAGCUUUCAUUAAAAUGUCAAAUCUCAUUAGACAUCAAAGAAUUCAUACUGGAGAGAAGCCCUAUGCAUGUAAGGAAUGUGAGAAGUCCUUCAGCCAGAAAUCAAAUCUUAUUGAUCAUGAAAAAAUUCAUACUGGAGAGAAACCUUAUGAAUGUAAUGAGUGUGGAAAAGCAUUCAGCCAGAAGCAAAGCCUCAUUGCACAUCAGAAAGUUCAUACUGGGGAGAAACCUUAUGCAUGUAAUGAAUGUGGUAAAGCCUUCCCUCGAAUUGCAUCCCUUGCUCUUCAUAUGAGAAGUCAUACAGGAGAAAAACCUUAUAAAUGUGAUAAAUGUGGUAAAGCCUUCUCUCAGUUUUCCAUGCUUAUUAUACAUGUUAGAAUUCAUACAGGUGAAAAACCCUAUGAAUGUAAUGAGUGUGGAAAAGCCUUCUCUCAAAGCUCAGCCCUUACUGUACAUAUGAGAAGUCACACUGGUGAGAAACCCUAUGAAUGUAAGGAAUGCAGAAAAGCCUUCAGCCACAAGAAAAACUUCAUUACACACCAGAAAAUUCAUACUAGAGAGAAACCUUAUGAGUGUAAUGAAUGUGGGAAAGCUUUUAUACAGAUGUCAAAUCUUGUUAGACACCAGAGAAUUCAUACUGGGGAAAAACCCUAUAUAUGUAAGGAAUGUGGGAAAGCCUUUAGCCAGAAAUCAAAUCUCAUUGCUCAUGAAAAAAUUCAUUCUGGAGAGAAACCCUAUGAAUGCAAUGAAUGUGGUAAAGCCUUCAGCCAAAAGCAAAACUUCAUUACACAUCAAAAAGUUCAUACUGGAGAGAAACCUUAUGAUUGUAAUGAAUGUGGUAAAGCCUUCUCUCAAAUUGCAUCCCUUACCCUUCAUUUGAGAAGUCAUACAGGGGAAAAGCCUUAUGAAUGUGAUAAAUGUGGUAAAGCCUUCUCUCAGUGCUCACUGCUUAAUUUACAUAUGAGAAGUCACACAGGUGAGAAGCCCUAUGUAUGUAAUGAAUGUGGGAAAGCCUUCUCUCAAAGAACUUCCCUUAUUGUGCACAUGAGAGGCCAUACAGGUGAAAAACCCUAUGAAUGUAAUAAAUGUGGAAAAGCCUUCUCCCAAAGCUCAUCCCUUACUAUACAUAUACGAGGACAUACAGGUGAGAAACCCUUCGACUGUAGUAAAUGUGGAAAAGCCUUCUCUCAAAUCUCAUCUCUUACCCUUCAUAUGAGAAAACAUACAGGUGAGAAGCCCUAUCACUGUAUUGAGUGUGGCAAGGCUUUCAGCCAAAAGUCGCACCUUGUUAGACACCAGAGAAUUCAUACUCAUUAGAAACCCUAUGAAUAUUGUGAAUAUGGCAAGGCCAUCUGAAGGAAUUAACACCUCAUUGCACAUUACAUGAUCACUUCCAGAGUAGAAAACUAUGAAUGUGGGAUAGCCUUCUGAAAAAGCCACAAAUUUAUGAAACAUUAGAGAAUUCUUCCAAGGUGACAAAUUAUAUAAUGAAAAAGCUGUUACCAGAAACUUUCAGCAGACAUCUUAUUGAUAAUAUUUAAUCAGCAUUCUCAUUGAAAUCUGAAACAAGGUAUCUUCCAUCAGCAUAACAACACAACACUUGAGCUCCUAGCCAAUGUAUUAAGUAAGGAAAACAAGUAUCAACGAAGAACUAUAAAAAUAACUUUUAUACAAGAAAUAAUUAGAAAAUGUGUUGAUAGAAAACCUAAGAAUAAACACAACAAUGAGUUAGGUCUUUAUCAAGUUAUAAAAUAUGUUGAAAGGCACAAAAGAACACCUGAAAAAUGAUAUUUUGUCUGAAAAGACUUGACAUUGUAAAAAUAUAAUUUCUCUCCCAAAUCACUAAGUUUAAUAUACUUCUGAAGUUUACAUCAGUUUUAUUUUAAGGAACUUCACAAACUUAUCCAAAAAUUUUAUGUGGAAAAGUAAAGAAACACAAAUAGCUGAAACAAACUUGACAAAGCAAGUAGAGAAGACACACUCUAUUAUUAGAUAUAUCAUGUACUUAUUUAAAGCUGCUGUCAUUUAAACAAUGUAUUACCAAGUGAAUAAAUCAAGCAGUAGUAAGAUAGUGAGCAUUCAUACAAAAAUCCAAGAAGAUACAGGAAUUCUGUGUAUGACAGUGCUAUUGAAAUCACUGGGGAAUGAAUGGCUUAUUUAAUAAAUGGAAGGUUCAUAGGAGAAAAAUUUUAGCUUUCUACUUUAUAUCAUAUACAAAAAUAAAAUCCAACUAAAGACCAGAAUAUAAAAAGCAAAAUUUUAAAACUAUGAUGAAAGUAGAAUCCGUUACUUUAGGGUAACAAGAUUUCUUUAAAAAACAUGUAAACAUGGAAUAGUCUGUUGAAUUUUGGUGUAUUGGCCUCACAGGCACCCACAAAUGUACACAAAGAGAUAUAUAUCACUGUGUUCCUGAAUCAUGGUUUGUAUUGCCCAAAAUUGGAUAUAACAAAUUUUUAUCAAUUGUGGAAUAGAUGAAUAAGUGUGAUCAUUUCUGUGAUAAAAUACAGAAUUUAGAAACAAAAUCUACCUAUAGUUAUAUGGAUAGAUUACAAUAUAUAAUAUUGAGAGAAAAAAUUAAAAUGCACAAAGGAACACAGUAUAACAUUUGUAUAAUUUAAUAAGAUCUUGCAAAGAACAGUACUGUGUAUUGGUCAUGGAUCCAUAUAUGACUUGGUUGCCUUUUGGGAUGUGGGAAAGGUUUGGUGGGAGUUGUUAUAUUUAUCUGUAAUAUUUCUUUAAUAAAAGAGUGAAAGCAAA